ACUGCCCUCCGGCCGCCGCGCCGCCCGCCCGCCGGGGCCCCGCUGUCCGCCGCCCGCCGCCGCUGGAGCUAGAGAUGGAUUUGCAGCCGCUGCAAGUGUGUGGAAGGGCCGUGUUCGUGUUGGCAAAGAAGGUCGGCUGCUGAGCCAGGGCGUGUCUCCCGGAGGCCUGUGGGCUGCCAGGAUCCCCACCUCUCUGCAAUGGGCUGCCCAGGCUGGUCAGUUACCAGCCAGUGACAUCAGCGAGGUUCCCUGCUCUCUACCCUGGGAAGGGCCCAGCCUAAGUUACCAAGCCCCAGGCUCCCAGUACCACCCUCAGCCUAUGUGGAUUGCCACCCCACCUUCUGCCUGUCCUUGGGAGGGGACCGACUCUUAGCUCCCCUUAGCAAUCAGGUUGCACCCAGUCCCUUGACUUUAUGCCCAGGUUUCCUGGCACCUAAAGUAGAAACGAUGCAACUGCCCCUCGGGCUUGCUGAGGGUCAAAGGGGGUGUGACUUUGUCAUGGAGCGUAGAAGUCAGAGUCGAUGGUGAUCCCGCUGGCUGUUAACAUCGAUACAGUUCAGGUCAGCAUGCACCAAGUUCCUCCAACACACCAGGUACAUUGGCUAGCCACCUCUCCCAGGCAGGGCGGUGCAGUGGUGAGAGCAGGGACCCCAGCCAGGUGGCCUGGGUCCUAACCCCCUGCACUGUCAUUGCUGGCUGUGGGACUCUGCACAAGGUACUGCACUUCUGUGCCUCAAUUUCCUCAUCUGUAGGGUGGGGGUGGUGAUUGCCACCCCAUAGGGUGGUUAUAAGGGGCCACACAUGUUCCUAUGUGUGAGAUGCUGAGAAAGUCACCUGGCAUGGACAGGAUGGACAGCCAGUAUUUAUCGAACUAUGAAUGAAUGAAUGUUACCCUUUAGUGGGUUCCAGCGUCCUAUCCUGUCGGUGGGAAGACUGAGGCUCAGAGAGCUCCGUAACUUGCCCCAGGUCACACAGCCGGUUCAGGCAGAGUUGGGGUCUCAUGCCUCCCAGGUGUUCCCACAGUCUUUUCCCCAGGAGCAGGGUCCAAGCCUGCUGCUCCUCCAACCACCUGCGAGGCACCUGGGCAUGUUCCUGGCCACCAGGAAAGAGAGGUCUAAUGGCAGUAGUACCAGUCAGCGUCAUGUGCCUGGAGCGAGUGCCCUACCAGCCGGUUCCUGCUGGAAGCUCCUGGUCUGAUCUGGGGAUACCAUGUCCAAGCCCCCCGACCUCCUGCUGCGGCUGCUCCGGGGCGCCCCAAGGCAGCGGGUCUGCACCCUGUUCAUCAUCGGCUUCAAGUUCACGUUUUUCGUCUCCAUCAUGAUCUACUGGCACGUUGUGGGAGAGCCCAAGGAGAAAGGGCAGCUCUAUAACCUGCCAGCAGAGAUCCCCUGCCCCACCUUGACACCCCCCACCCCACCCUCCCACGGCCCCACUCCAGGCAACAUCUUCUUCCUGGAGACUUCAGACCGGACCAACCCCAACUUCCUGUUCAUGUGCUCGGUGGAGUCGGCCGCCAGAACUCACCCCGAAUCCCACGUGCUGGUCCUGAUGAAAGGGCUUCCGGGUGGCAACGCCUCUCUGCCCCGGCACCUGGGCAUCUCACUUCUGAGCUGCUUCCCGAAUGUCCAGAUGCUCCCGCUGGACCUGCGGGAGCUGUUCCGGGACACACCCCUGGCCGACUGGUACGCGGCCGUGCAGGGGCGCUGGGAGCCCUACCUGCUGCCCGUGCUCUCCGACGCCUCCAGGAUCGCACUCAUGUGGAAGUUCGGCGGCAUCUACCUGGACACGGACUUCAUUGUUCUCAAGAACCUGCGGAACCUGACCAACGUGCUGGGCACCCAGUCCCGCUACGUCCUCAACGGCGCGUUCCUGGCCUUCGAGCGCCGGCACGAGUUCAUGGCGCUGUGCAUGCGGGACUUCGUGGACCACUACAACGGCUGGAUCUGGGGUCACCAGGGCCCGCAGCUGCUCACGCGGGUCUUCAAGAAGUGGUGUUCCAUCCGCAGCCUGGCCGAGAGCCGCGCCUGCCGCGGCGUCACCACCCUGCCCCCUGAGGCCUUCUACCCCAUCCCCUGGCAGGACUGGAAGAAGUACUUUGAGGACAUCAACCCCGAGGAGCUGCCGCGGCUGCUCAGUGCCACCUAUGCUGUCCACGUGUGGAACAAGAAGAGCCAGGGCACGCGGUUCGAGGCCACGUCCAGGGCACUGCUGGCCCAGCUGCAUGCCCGCUACUGCCCCACGACGCACGAGGCCAUGAAAAUGUACUUGUGAGGGGCCCGCCAGGUCACCUCCCCAACCUGCUCCUGAUGGGGCACUGGGCCGCCCUUCCCGGGGAGGCAAGAUUGAGGGCCCGGGAGAGGGAGGCCCGAGCUGCCACCGGGCUUAGGCAGGCUGUUGAGGAGCUGUGGGAGCAGGCCCAGUGGGAGGCUGUGGACACCCCGAGGACAGUGUCCUGUCUCGAGGCAGGGCUGACACAUGGUGCCAUAGCCAGCGGAGGGCGCUCAGUGAGUGCCCCGGGCCUUCUAGACAACAGGCAGGAAGGAUGAACCUCAGGGCACCCCCAGGUGGUGCGGAAAGCCAGGCAGUUGGGACAGAGGUGCCCACGAGGGCAGAGGCCGGUGCUAAGGGGAUGGGGAAGAAGGGACAAGAUUCCCAGAGAGGAGAGGAGGCUGUUGGUAGGAAAGUGGCAGGGCUGGGGGAGACCCAGCCCCAAGGGUCCGGGGCGGAGGAUGCUUUGUUCUUUUCUGGUUUUGGUUCCUCUUUCGCGGGGGGUGGGGGAGGUCAACAGGGACUGAGUGGGGCAGAGGCCCAGAAGUGCCAGCCUGGGGAGCCGUUUGGGGGCAGCCCCUUCUGCCCACCCCAUCCUUCUUCCUCUCCAGAGAUGCCAGGGGGGCGUGUAUGCUCUGCCCCUUCCCUCAGACAGGGGCUGGGUGGGGAGGCUCUUUAGGCUCAGGAGAAGCAUUUUAAAGAAACCCCCACCCUGCCGCCCGCAUUAUAAACACAGGAGAAUAAUCAAUAGAAUAAAAGUGACCGACUGUCA